GAAAGCUAAAGGCCGGCGCACGCUGGGCGGUGGUGGUCCCUAAGCCGGGCCGCGGCCGGUGCAAUGGACUCCACUGCCUGCUUGAAGUCCUUGCUCCUGACUGUCAGUCAGUACAAAGCCGUGAAGUCAGAGGCGAACGCCACUCAGCUUUUGCGGCACUUGGAGGUAAUUUCUGGACAGAAACUCACACGACUAUUUACAUCAAAUCAGAUAUUAACAAGUGAAUGCUUGAGUUGCCUUGUAGAGCUACUUGAAGACCCCAACAUAAGUGCUUCACUGAUCUUAAGUAUUAUCGGUUUGCUGUCUCAACUAGCAGUAGACAUUGAAACCAGAGAUUGUCUUCAGAAUACAUAUAAUCUGAAUAGUGUGCUGGCGGGAGUGGUUUGUCGGAGCAGCCACACUGAUUCGGUGUUUUUGCAGUGCAUUCAACUUCUACAGAAGUUAACAUAUAAUGUCAAAAUUUUCUAUUCUGGUGCCAAUAUAGAUGAAUUAAUUACGUUCCUGAUAGAUCACAUUCAAUCUUCUGAAGAUGAGUUAAAAAUGCCUUGUCUAGGAUUAUUGGCAAAUCUUUGUCGGCACAAUCUUUCUGUUCAAACGCACAUAAAGACAUUGAGUAAUGUGAAAUCUUUUUAUCGAACUCUUAUCACCUUGUUGGCCCAUAGUAGUUUAACUGUGGUUGUGUUUGCACUUUCAAUAUUAUCCAGUUUGACAUUAAAUGAAGAGGUGGGGGAAAAGCUAUUCCAUGCUCGAAACAUUCAUCAGACUUUUCAACUAAUAUUUAAUAUUCUCAUAAACGGUGAUGGCACUCUAACUAGAAAGUAUUCAGUUGACCUACUGAUGGAUCUCCUUAAGAAUCCUAAAAUUGCUGAUUAUCUCACCAGAUAUGAGCACUUUUCUUCAUGUCUUCACCAAGUAUUAGGUCUUCUUAAUGGAAAGGAUCCUGAUUCCUCUUCAAAGGUUUUAGAAUUACUUCUUGCCUUCUGUUCAGUGACUCAGCUGCGCCAUAUGCUCACUCAGAUGAUGUUUGAACAGUCUCCACCUGGCAGCGCCACUCUGGGAAGCCAUACUAAAUGUUUAGAACCUACUGUGGCUCUACUGCGCUGGUUAAGCCAACCUUUGGACGGAUCAGAAAACUGUUCUGUUUUAGCAUUGGAGUUGUUCAAGGAAAUAUUUGAGGAUGUCAUAGAUGCUGCUAACUGUUCCUCGGCUGAUCGUUUUGUGACCCUUCUGCUGCCUACAAUCCUUGAUCAACUUCAGUUCACAGAACAAAAUCUAGAUGAGGCUUUAACAAGAAAAAAAUGUGAAAGGAUUGCCAAGGCCAUUGAAGUUUUGUUAACUCUCUGUGGAGAUGAUACACUAAAAAUGCAUAUUGCAAAAAUCUUGACAACUGUCAAGUGUACCACUCUUAUAGAACAACAAUUUACAUAUGGCAAGAUUGACCUGGGAUUUGGAACAAAGGUUGCAGAUUCUGAAUUAUGCAAACUUGCUGCUGAUGUAAUUUUGAAAACUCUUGAUUUGAUUAACAAACUUAAACCAUUGGUUCCUGGUAUGGAAGUAAGCUUCUACAAAAUACUUCAGGACCCACGUUUGAUUACUCCUUUGGCUUUUGCUUUAACGUCAGAUAAUAGAGAACAAGUACAGUCUGGACUGAGAAUAUUAUUGGAGGCUGCUCCACUGCCAGAUUUUCCUGCUUUAGUACUUGGAGAAAGUAUAGCAGCAAACAAUGCCUAUAGACAACAGGAAACAGAACAUAUACCCAGAAAAAUGCCCUGGCAAUCAUCAAAUCACAGUUUUCCAACAUCAAUAAAGUGUUUAACUCCUCAUUUGAAAGAUGGUGUUCCUGGAUUGAAUAUUGAAGAAUUAAUAGAGAAACUUCAGUCUGGAAUGGUGGUAAAGGAUCAGAUUUGUGAUGUGAGAAUAUCUGACAUAAUGGAUGUAUAUGAAAUGAAACUAUCCACAUUAGCUUCCAAAGAAAGCAGGCUACAAGAUCUUUUGGAAACAAAAGCUCUAGCCCUUGCACAGGCUGAUAGACUGAUUGCUCAGCAUCGCUGUCAAAGAACUCAAGCUGAAACAGAGGCACGGACACUUGCUAGUAUGUUGAGAGAAGUUGAGAGAAAAAAUGAAGAGCUUAGUGUGUUGCUGAAGGCGCAGCAAGUUGAAUCAGAAAGAGCGCAGAGUGAUAUUGAGCAUCUCUUUCAACAUAAUAGGAAGUUAGAGUCUGUGGCUGAAGAACAUGAAAUACUGACAAAAUCCUACAUGGAACUUCUUCAGAGAAAUGAAAGUACUGAAAAGAAGAAUAAAGAUUUACAGAUCACAUGUGAUUCUCUGAAUAAACAAAUUGAGACAGUGAAAAAGUUGAAUGAGUCACUCAAGGAACAAAAUGAAAAAAGUAUUGCCCAAUUAAUAGAGAAAGAAGAACAGAGAAAAGAAGUACAGAAUCAGCUAGUAGACAGAGAACAUAAGCUAGCAAAUUUGCAUCAAAAAACAAAAGUACAAGAAGAAAAGAUUAAAACCUUACAAAAGGAAAGGGAAGAUAAGGAAGAAACCAUUGAUAUCCUUAGAAAAGAAUUAAGCAGAACAGAACAGAUAAGAAAAGAGUUGAGCAUUAAGGCUUCCUCCCUAGAGGUUCAAAAGGCACAAUUAGAAGGUCGUUUGGAAGAGAAAGAGUCCUUGGUGAAACUUCAGCAAGAGGAAUUGAACAAACACUCCCACAUGAUAGCAAUGAUCCACAGUUUAAGUGGUGGAAAAAUAAAUCCAGAAACUGUGAAUCUCAGUAUAUAGACAUUAUGGCAUUUUGGAAUUUGUAAUCUCAUGAUAUUUUUGAUGUAUUUAUCUAUUGGAGGGGGGGUGGGUAGGGGAGUUAAUUUGUGACUUCGUAACAAUAAGAAGUUAUUAUCUAAUUUAGUAAAGACCCUGAUCUGUUGCAUGUUUUUUAUUUGAUAGUUUGAAUAGAAAUUUAAUUUUCUAAGUUUUACUUUUUGUUUCUGGCUUUUAUGGCUUAAGGUUUUCUUUGGUUCUUACAUUAGAAAAUCAUUUUUAACCUCCAUUAUCAUUUUUCUAAGGUUCUUUCCUUUUUCUUAGUUGCUUUCUAUUCUGUUUUGCCUGUCUUAUUUAUUCUCAUUUGUGAUUAUUUAGAUCUUAAGACCAAACUUUCUUGGUAUAACAGUCCUAAAGAUUACAAAAUAAAAAUAUAGAGAGAGUAAAAGUAAAAAGUAAAGUAAAAAGAGAGAAGGUAUGAUUUUACUGCUAGAGAAGUUUGUCUCUGAAGAAGCACAAAAGAAAAUAUUAGUGAAUUUAAAAUAAUUUUUAUACUGCUGUAGCAUAAUUUCUAAAUUUGAAAAAAAUGCAAUGGUAAUAAAAUGUAUAAAAAUUAGAAAACUGUCAUUGUGUUAAACUAUUACAUUUAAAUGAUUACAUUUAACACAAUAGCUGUCUCAUAAAAAAUCUAAGAACUUGUAGAAUUAUUUGUAAGGUAUAUUUAGUGUUUUUUUCUCUUUUUUCAAAUGUUGCAUAGUGGUCCAGAUCAUCUAUAAUUAAUUAUAAGUUUCUUAUGAUUUACAUAAGGAUAAUUUGGAUUCUACUCUUGCUGCAUAUUCAGAAAAAUAUUAUUUACUGUUAAUUCUGAUAUGAAUUGUAUUUAAUUUGUUGUCCUAAUAGUUUUUAAUUGGUUCAUUUAAUUUUAAAGCAUAGGUUAAAUAUCUUUAUUUUUUUUAAAAUACAAGGGUCCUUCUGUACUUUUCAUUUGAAUCAUAUCCUCUAACUACUCUGUAAGAAACGUUUUUACAUCAAUAUUUUGAUUGAUUUUAUUGCUAUACCAAUACAGUCAUUAAUUUUACUUGGUGUUUUCUUCACCAUAUGUCUGUUUGAUUUAAGUGAAUUUAGAUUUGUACAGUUCUGGAAAUUUUUUAAAAAAUAUUAUGCAGAGUAAAACAUUUUAAAUUACUAUUUGUUCUAUAGAGGAGAUACAUUCUGUUUCUCUUUUGAAAUUGCAUGCAUUUUCAACCAAAUAUGAAAAAGUUUAAGUGGAUAGAUAAGACUGAAGAAUAAAAGGGUCUAUAAAAUAAAA